ACAAGUAGUACUUCACAUCUUGAUAGACCUUGCUUUGUUUUGUUUUCAUCUGCUUACUUGAACUAGCCCACCAUUAUGAUUUCAACUUCUCCUGGUAUUCUGUCGAUGGUGUAAGUUUCUUGUAUGGGUUGGAACCCCGAGAGCGCACCAACAGACAACACGAGGCGGUGUGGAGCAACAUGCUGUUUCAAUGAACGCCUUGGUGCAGGCCGGCUGAGGCCUAAAAUGGCGUCAGCCCCAAGUGAGGACGGGGCAAAGGUUUUAUAGUCUCCUGUAAACAGGAAGUGUCCUAGUCUGGCGUAACUGCUACGCUGUACCCGGAUGGCCUCUUUCUCAUCUUCAUGUCUUCCGGCCAGGGUAGGUGUAUUCCAGCCGGCUCUCCUCCUGCUUCUGCUAUUUUGCUGGUGCACGCUGCUGACGUCAGAAGGGAAAAUAUGCAAGUUUGAUUGAAAAAUAUAAGAAACACCCUAAAACAGACAGUUCUGUUACAAAGAUGCGUCGUUUUUACCACAUUGAGUAUUUCCUUCUGCCGGACGAUGAAGAACCUAAAAAAGUUGACAUAUUGCUAUUUCCAAUGGUGGCCAAAGUAUUCCUGGAGUCAGGAGUAAAGACUGUGAAGCCGUGGCACGAAGGUGACAAAGCCUGGGUGUCGUGGGAGCAGACUUUUAAUAUCACUGUGACAAAGGAAUUAUUAAAGAAAAUAAAUUUCCACAAAAUCACCUUGAGGCUCUGGAACACUAAAGACAAGAUGUCAAGAAAAGUCAGAUAUUACCGAUUAAAGACUGCCGGCUUCACAGACGACGUGGGAGCUUUUCAUAAGUCAGAAGUGAGACAUUUGGUUUUAAAUCAGAGAAAAUUAUCUGAACAGGGCAUUGAGAAUACCAACAUUGUCAGAGAAGAGUCGAACCAGGAACAUCCGCCAGGAAAACAAGAAAAAACAGAAAAACACCCAAAGUCUUUGCAAGGUUCUCACCAAGCAGAGCCCGAAACUUCUUCCAAGAACAGUGAGGAAUAUGAGAAGUCCCUCAAAAUGGACGAUUCUUCCACGAUUCAAUGGAGUGUUUCAAGAACACCAACCAUUUCUUUGGCAGGAGCAAGCAUGAUGGAGAUCAAGGAAUUAAUUGAGAGUGAAUCACUUAGCAGCUUAACAAACAUAUUAGACAGACAAAGGUCUCAAAUUAAAGGGAAAGAUUCAGAGGGAAGAAGGAAAAUCCAGAGGAGACAUAAGAAGCCCCUGGCAGAAGAAGAGGCAGACCCCACGCUGACAGGCCCCAGGAAGCAGAGCGCUUUCUCCAUCCAGCUGGCCGUCAUGCCGCUCCUUGCCGGUACCCACUGCUUGCCCUGUUCCCAGCAGCUCCUGCUUGUCUUGUGGCCAGAACGGCCAUAAGCGGAUGCUCCUAAUGACAACCCUGCUGCGUGCCACCUCAUUUCAUCCUCACAGCCACCUCAGGAAACUCAGGGGAAUUGGCUUCAUAGUACAGGGGGAAACAAAGGCCCAGAGAGGGUAGCUACCUUGCCUGAGAUCACACAGCUAGGAAAUGUGAAGCCUGGACUUGAACCCAGCUCUGUUUGAUUCCAAAAUCCAAGGAAGCCUAUGGGAAUAUUAAAUGUCAUCAUUGUGUUUGUUAAGAAGAUGCUGCUUUUAAUAAAUGCUUUCCUACAGAUUUUUACAAAAACAUCUAGUAAAGGGAAUGAGGAAAGGGAACCCUUUUUGACUGAGCCCCUCUGGGUGCAGGCACUUCCCGUGUGACACAUCACUUACUUCUCAGACCAAAUUCUGACCCACUCAGCCAACCUGUGGUGUGGUGGUGGCUGUGGUGGUUAUCAUAGUUACCAUUUUUUUCAGUGAGGAAAAGAACUCAAAGAGGUUAAGUAACUUUCCUAAUCCCACACAGCUCAGUGGCCAAACAGGGAUUUAAUUAUUUUGCUUUAUAAGAUCUACCACAAUUUAUGAACUGGACUUUAUACAUACUGGUAAAUCAUAACUAAAUAUUAUAUCAAUAUGUUUUGAUGAUUGAAAGCUCAGCAUAUAUUUUGGUAAAAUUAUGUUGCUUUGUUCCAAAAAAGAGUAAUAUGGGGUGAACUCCCCCCCUUUUUUUUUCUUUUUAGAGAAAAUUCAGACUUUGUUCGUUUUUUUGCCAUCACGUGUCUUGUGCGCCCUCUCCUGGCUACUCUGCAGAAGCGCGUGCGUUGGUCUUUUCUGAGCUGGAACCAGCAUUCAUAGAGAAGGGGGCAAAAACCCCGUAAGUCAGAGCCUCCAGUUCAGUUCCACAGGUGCCAGUCGUCAUCCUCCUCUCGCGCUCUUGGGUUGGUGUCAAUUCAGUUUGAGAAAGUGCUAUUAACUUUUCAGUUUGCACUUUUUUUUUUUUUGAGAUAGGGUCUUGCUCUCUCACCCAGGCUGGAGUGUAAGUGACAUGAUCAUAGCUCACUCCAGCCUGAAGCAAGCCUCCCGCCUCUGCCACCCGCAUAGCUAAGACUACAGGUGCACACCACCACACCUGGCUAUUUUUUUUAUUUUCUGUAGAGACAAGGUCUUGCUAUGUUGCCCAGGCUGGUCUCAAACUCCUGGUCACAAGUAAUCCUCCUGCUUCAGCCUCUCAGAGUUCUAGAAUUACAGGCAUGAGCUGCCGCAUUUGGCAGUUUGCAGUUUUAAAUGACUUUUUGAAAAUGAUACUUCACCUACAGCUUGUCCUUCCUGAUCACCUUCACUUUCUCGUAGCAUCAGAACCUCUUGAGAGGCAACAGUGACAGAGAGUAAACUUUCAGAGGGUCUUACCCCACCCCACGCUCCAGCCUGACCCUCCAGCAUACCUAUUGCACACAGUAGCUUUGAGCGAACGCCUUUGCUAGCUGCUUCCUUCGUCCUACAGUCCCAAGGAGGAACCCAUGAUCCUCCUGGGGGAGCGUACCAUGGGACCUGCCCCGCUUUGGAUUUUACUGUGAGAGGAAAAAGAAGUUCAACCAUUUGGGCCUGCCUGGCAUGACUGUUUCCAGCAGAAUGAAGCCAGGACAUGGUCCCCUCUCUCUUUUUUUUUUUUCGAGAUGGAGUCUUGCUCUGUCGCCCAGGCUGGAGUGCAGUGGCGCGAUCUCGGCUCACUACAGCCUCUGCCCCCCCAGGUUUAAGCAAUUCUCCUGCUUCAACCUCUAGAGUAGCUGGGAUUACAGGCGCAUGCCACCAUGCCAGGCUAAUUUUUGUAUUUUUUGUAGAGAUGGGGUUUCACAAUUUUGGCCAGGCUGGUCUUGAACUCCUGACCUCGUGAUUGUCUUACAUGUCCGUGUGAAGAGACCAAACAGGCUUUGUGUAAGUAACAAGGCUGUUUAUUUCACCUGGGUGCAGGCAGGCUGAGUCUGAAAAGAGAGUCAGCAAAGGGUGGUGGGAUUAUCAUUAGUUCUUACAGGUUUUGGGAUAGGCAGUGGAGUUAAGAGCAAUGUUUUGGGGGCAGGGGGUGGAUCUCACAAAGUACAUUCUCAAGGGUGGGGAGAAUUACAAAAAAACCUUCUUAAGGGUGGGGGAGAUUAUAAAGAACCUUCUUAAGUGUGGGGGAGAUUACAAAGUACAUUGAUAGUUAGGGUGGGGCAGAAACAAAUCACAAUGGUGGAAUGUCAUCAGUUAAGGCUAUUUUCACUUCUUUUGUGGAUCUUCAGUUGCUUCAGGCCAUCUGGAUGUAUACAUGCAGGUCACUGGGGAUAUGAUGGCUUAGCUUGGGCUCAGAGGCCUGACAGUGAUCCACCUGCCUCAGCCUCCCAAAGUGCUGGGAUUACAGGCGUGAGCUACCGCACUGGACCUAGCCUCCCCUCUCUAUAACCUGCCCCGUCAUGUACAAUGCUGUACAGUGCAGGGGUUCACAUGUAAGAACUUUGGUGACCAAAACACUUUGAUCAUGGCUCAGCCACUUACCAGCAAGUUACCUACUUUCUCUGAGUCUCACUUUCCUCCUCUGUGAAAUGGGGGUGAUUACUCCUACCUCAGAGCGUUGUUUUAAGGAUCACAGGAGCUGACGUGUGUAAACUGCUAGCACAGUGGGACCCAGGGGGUGCAGGUGUGGAGGCAGCAGCUGUCCUGAGGCCAUGUGUGUGGGCCGCUCCAUUAUACCCAUGACAUAGCCUAUGGUCAUCGACAGAGAACGGGUCAGCUCAGCAGGCCAGUUGUAUGUCUGGUUUUGCCAGAAACUAAUAGCAUAAGAUUAUUUACUGUAAGCCCAGCAUAAUUAUUUUUGGUAAUCAUCUUCAAUUUCAAAUUAGGCCAUAGAUCAUGUAUGUAUACCUUAUUAGUAAAUAUUGGUUGGCUAGUAACCCAGUAAGAUUCUAGAAAGAUUCUGUGUCUGGGAAUGAGCUCUUAUUUUAAAAGGAUAGUAUUGCAUAGCGGAGGGGCCCCACUUAGCCCAACAGAACUGGUUUGGAUGCUGGUUCUACAACGUAUUUUCUAAGAGACCUUGGAUGAUUGCGUCAGAACUCUGGGCCUCAUUUCCCCCAUCUGUAAUGUGGAGAUGACAGCAACCACACAAGGUUAAGGAUGAAAUGACAUUAGCGCAUGUUUGGGACUGGCUGUUGGAGGAGCACAAACAUUCCCUUACACCAUUCCACUCUUAACCAGGGCUCUUAACUCAGGGGGCUUGUGUCUGCUGGGGACACUUGGCUGUGUGUGGAGGCAUUUUGGUUGGCACGACUGAGAGUGGGAUGCCACUGGCAUCUAGUAAGAUACUGUUAAACAUGCCAUAAUGCACAGGACUGUCCCCUGAGCAAAGAAUGGUCUGCCCCAACUGUCAGCAGUGUGGAGGCUGUGAGCCCGCAGCCUGGAAUUCUGUUCUGGUGUAUGUCUCCCUGACUCUGAUGAUUUGAGCACUUUUUUUUUAUUUUUAUUUUUGCAAUGGGGAUUCCUUCUACCUUGAGUAGUCUUUUUUUUUUUUUUGAGACGGAGUUUUGCUCUUGUUGCCCAGGCUGGAGUACAAUGGCGCGAUCUCAGCUCACCGCAACCUCCGCCUCCCGGGUUCAAGCGAUUCUCCUGCAUUAGCCUUCCUGAGUAGUUGGGAAUACAGGCAUGCGCUACCACGUCCGGCUGAUUUUGUAUUUUUGGUAGAGACGAGGUUUCUCCAUUUUGGUCAGGCUGGUCUCAAACUCCCGACUUCAGGUGAUCCGCCUGCCUCGGCCUGCCAAACUGCUGGGAUUAUAGGCGUGAGCCACCGUACCCGGCCUACCCUUGGGUAGUCUUUCAUGUGAAAAGGCUCACAAAAUUAUAGAACACAGGCGUAAUGGGUGACAGCUUUUAUGAAUCAGCUUUGUUAAAGAGGAUCCUGCGGGAGCAUGAGGGCUACCCCCAGGAGCUGUGCACGCCUCUGUUCACAGCCUGUGCAGAUGGCUGUGCACACCUGGCCCGGGACUUGUUUUAGAAGUGCCUACUCUUUCUGAAUGUGAGCGACUUGGCUUUUACAUGCCCUAGAAAUACAUUUACAGGCAUGUUGAAAGGAAUAGACUGAUCUUUUUGAGCACCAUCUCAUAUAUCAUCUUUCUUAAUCCUUUAAACCCAAGGAAGGUGGUGUCUAUCCCCAUUUUGAAGAUGAAAUUGAGCCUUGGAGACUCUAGCUUAUCACAUGACAAAGAGUCAGAUCUGGGAUUCAAACCCAGGUCAAUCCUGCCUCCAAAACUUGAGGUGAUUUUUUUUGUUUAUUUGUUUUGUUUUUUCCUUACCUAGUACAUCUCUGACUGGUGAAAUACAUGGAUACCUUUUAUAGAAAAAGCAUUCUGGGCUGGGUGUGGUGGCUCACGCCUGUAAUCCCUACACUUUGGGAGGCCGAGGCGGGUGGAUCACGAGGUCAGGAGAUCGAGAACAGCCUGGCUAACACGGUGAAACCCCGUCUUUACUAACAAUACAAAAAAUUAGCCAGGCAUGUUGUCGGGCACCUGUAGUCCCAGCUACUUGGGAGGCUGAGGCAGGAGAAUGGCGUGAACCCAGGAGGCGUAGCUAGCAGUGAGCCAAGACCGUGCCACUGUACUCCAGCCUGGGCAGCAGAGCAAGACUCUGUCUC